GCAUUGUGGGUUCUCCUGGAGCUGUGGAGUUGAUCCUGAAUGAAAGUGGCGCGCCGCCCCUGACGUUACCCGGAUCGGAGAGGUUGGAAUUCAGAUUACGGCUGCGAUUCGGGUGUCUCGGACCCCGGUGUGCACCGGACCACGGGGAGGCGGCUCCAAAGGCGCGGUGAACGUUGGUGAGGGAGGGCAGCUCUGCGCAGCCCCAAGACAUGGCUCACAACAAGAUCCCGCCGCGGUGGCUGAACUGUCCCCGGCGCGGCCAGCCGGUGGCAGGAAGAUUCUUACCUCUGAAGACAAUGUUAGGACCAAGAUAUGAUAGUCAAGUUGCUGAAGAAAAUCGGUUCCAUCCCAGCAUGCUCUCAAAUUACCUAAAGAGCCUAAAGGUUAAAAUGGGCUUGUUGGUGGACCUGACAAAUACUUCAAGGUUCUAUGACCGAAAUGACAUAGAAAAAGAAGGAAUCAAAUAUAUAAAACUUCAGUGUAAAGGACAUGGUGAGUGCCCUACCACUGAGAAUACUGAGACCUUUAUUCGUCUGUGUGAGCGGUUUAAUGAAAGAAAUCCACCUGAACUUAUAGGUGUUCAUUGUACUCAUGGCUUCAAUCGCACUGGUUUCCUCAUAUGUGCCUUUUUGGUGGAGAAAAUGGAUUGGAGUAUCGAAGCAGCAGUUGCUACUUUUGCCCAAGCCAGACCACCAGGAAUCUACAAGGGUGAUUAUUUGAAGGAACUUUUUCGUCGGUAUGGUGACAUAGAGGAAGCACCACCCCCACCUCUAUUGCCAGAUUGGUGUUUUGAGGAUGAUGAAGACGAAGAUGAGGAUGAGGAUGGAAAGAAGGAAUCAGAACCCGGGUCAAGUGCUUCUUUUGGCAAAAGGAGAAAAGAACGGUUAAAACUGGGCGCUAUUUUCUUGGAAGGUGUUACUGUUAAAGGUGUAACUCAAGUAACAACACAACCAAAGUUAGGAGAGGUACAGCAGAAGUGUCAUCAAUUCUGUGGCUGGGAAGGGUCUGGAUUCCCUGGAGCACAGCCUGUUUCCAUGGACAAGCAAAAUAUUAAACUUUUAGACCUGAAGCCAUACAAAGUAAGCUGGAAAGCAGAUGGUACUCGGUACAUGAUGUUGAUUGAUGGCACAAAUGAAGUUUUUAUGAUUGAUAGAGACAAUUCAGUAUUUCAUGUUUCAAAUCUGGAAUUUCCAUUUCGUAAAGAUCUUCGUAUGCAUUUAUCAAAUACUCUCUUGGAUGGCGAGAUGAUUAUUGACAGAGUAAAUGGACAGGCUGUUCCUAGAUAUUUGAUAUAUGACAUAAUUAAAUUCAAUUCACAGCCCGUUGGAGAUUGUGAUUUUAAUGUUCGUCUGCAGUGUAUAGAACGAGAAAUUAUAAGUCCUCGACACGAAAAAAUGAAGACUGGGCUCAUUGACAAAACACAGGAACCAUUUAGCGUCAGAAAUAAGCCGUUUUUUGACAUCUGUACUUCAAGAAAGCUACUUGAAGGAAAUUUUGCCAAAGAAGUGAGCCAUGAAAUGGAUGGACUUAUUUUUCAGCCUACUGGAAAAUACAAACCUGGUCGAUGUGAUGAUAUUUUGAAAUGGAAGCCUCCCAGUCUGAAUUCUGUGGAUUUUCGUCUAAAAAUAACAAGAAUGGGAGGAGAAGGGUUACUUCCUCAGAAUGUUGGCCUCCUGUAUGUUGGAGGUUAUGAAAGACCCUUUGCACAAAUCAAGAAUUCAGAACAAGUUAAAUCCACAGGAGACUACAACCAAACUGGCUUCCCUAAAAGAACUGCAUCAACUCCAAGGUUGGAGAUAAAGCGCAUUCAACAUACCAUCUUUCCAAGAUGUGGGAAGAAUAAGAUAUUCUUAUCAAUGAAGCACAAGAACCUGUGGAAUCAGAAAGGGCUUUCCAGAGAAAGUGAUCCUGGUGGAAGAACUGGCUAUCCAGAGGGGAGGAUGCAAUGCCAUUCAGGGGGAAGAGUAAGAACAGAGUCCUAGAGCAAGAGACCCUGGUCCAAGGAUGAAAGCCAUGUAAUGUUUUAAAAUCUGAUGUCAUUUCUAUAAUUCCUUUGUAUAAUGUUCAUCAAGCUUUUUUUUUUCUACACAUACUUAUUGAGCACCUUUUAUGUAUUCAGUGGGGGGAUCUGGCAAUGAACAAAAUGACUUGUUUUGUUCACUCAAGGAGCUUACCAUCUAAUGGGGGUGCAUGUAAAUGAAAGGAAGGGAUUAUACCCUGCAAUAAUAUGUCAUGAUAUUUCAGGAUUUGACAAAACAGACUCAGUUCUGUAGAGAAAAAUGCUAUCUGAAAUUUAAAUUAAAGCCAAGCAUCAACUAUGCUUUGGUAGCAAUGUUAUACCAGAAGGACUACAGAAGAAAUGGGUGAGAGCAUUUGCCCAGCCAGGACAGCCUCUUUACAGUGUAGUCAUUGUUCGAAAAGAGACAAUAUGUGGGAAAGGAAGGUGGCAGAAGCCAUGAGACGGGGUCUGAUUUAGCAUUCUGAGUACCAAGACUCCUGUCCUGAGAGUUGUCUACCUUUAUUGUUUAUAAAAUUCAAGAUUAGAAUUAUACUAGACUAGAAUUAACUUCCAUGCUAGUUGCUUGAAAUCAAUCCAUUAUUCUGUUUGAUAUUCUGUGAGAUUUUUUUCCCCCCUGACUUUGAUGGUUGGUUUCGAAAUCCAUUAAGUGGAUCUCAAUCAGGUUUGUUUGUUUGUUUUUGUUUUAAUGAAAUAAAGUAGAAGAGAAAAUAGCACAAAGAAAGGAAAUAAAUUGCUUUAUGAAAUGUACGUGUGUGUGUGUGUGUGUGUGUGUGUGUGUGUGUGUCUGUGUGUCUGUGUGUCUGUAGUUGGUUGCUAUAUAAACUGUUUUUCUUGCAUUAGAUAAACUGGAUCAAACUUAAAUGACUGUAAGUAAACAUUUGCCCUGCAAAGUUAUACCUUUUGUUUAUGAAGGAUUGUCUUAUAGAUGACUCCAUAGUCAGUGUGCUGGACUGGGAUGCUGCAAGUCUGGACCCUGGUGCUAGUUCUGCACCCAAAGAGGCAUAUGCUUUGGAUAAGUUAUAGGCUUUCUGUGAACCUUAGUGUUUUCCAUCUAAAAAGAGAGUUGGGGCUGAGCAUGGUGGCUUAUGUCUGUAAUCACAGCACUUUGGGAGGCUAAGGCAGAUGGGUUGCUUCAGCCCGGGUGUUUGAGACCAGCCUGGGCAACAUGGUGAAACUCCCAUCUCUACAAAAAAUACAAAAAUUAGCCAAGUGUGGUGGCACACGCCUGUAGUUCCAGCUGCUAGCAAAGCUGAGGUGGGAGUAUCACUUGAGCCUGGGAGGUUGAGGCUGCAGUGAGCUGUGAGCGUCCCACACCACUCUAGCUUGGGCGACAGAGCAAGACCUUGUCUCAAAAUAAUAAAUAAAGAGUUGGCCUAGGUGGACUUGGUACUCUUUCAGAAGCAGUUGGCUAUAAAAAAUCAGUUGUCUUAAAGUUGAUUGGACAUUUUCACAGUUCUCUGUUACUAACUCAGAGAAGUGUUUCUAGGAGGUUAAAAAAAAACUUGAAACAAAAAAUAUAUAUAGCCUACUAUCACAUGAUUCUGGUUCCUGACGGAUGCUUUUCUCCCAACCUCCAUCCAAAAGUAUAUGGUCCACUGCAGGCAAACAGAUCUUCUGAAUGAAAUAAGGGGCAUAAAAACACAUGGGAUGGUACCUGCAUCAUAGGGCCUUAAAAAAAAAAUGUAGAGUUGAGAAAAUGUUGCUCAAGAUCUCAGCUCCUGCACUGGCCACCAUCAUAUGGGCUACUUGUCACAAAAGCGAGGAAGUCAUGAGAGGGAGGGAGGGACACCUCUAGAGCCUUUAUUCAUUUCCAUUUAUCGGAUCUGCAUAUAAGUGCUCCCUUACUCCUUUGUGAGAUGUCAAGGUGAUAGAAGGCAUCUUCCAGGUACCUUUUCACCACUGCAUGCAGUAGGGAACAUCAAAUACCAGAGGGAUUCUGCAGUCUCAACCCCUUUGGUGUAAAGACUACCUAAAAAGACAAUCCAGCCAUAUAAAAAGUAACAGCCCAUUUAUCUCAUUCAUAUGUUUAAGGUCAGUUUUCCUGUAGGAGAUCUCUGAGACAGUAGCAAUUAAACUGAGCUGUAUGUAGCAACAUAGUACAUGCUACAAACUAAGUUAAAAUUGUCAAAGAACUUUUCGUUUGUAGCAGUUUCUUAAUGUUAUGAGGCACAGAACUGUGUGGCCAUCAGAAAGACAGAGCUGCUAACAACUCCAUUUGGGGCAUUGUUAGGCAGUUCUGUUGACACAUGAAUACAUUUCAUAUGAUUAUCAUAAAAUUGUGGCCUGGAAAUUGAGCAGCCAUGGUGCUGCAUUUUAGACUUCACAUUUAUAAUAAGCUGUAAUAAAGUAAACAUUUUAAAUGGAUAUAAGAAUAGACAUUACUUGCAAUCACAAAUGUAUGUUCAAUUGAAGUGCUUUUGAAGCUCAAUUUAACAAAGCAAACAAAUUUCCUGGCAUUAUUAACAUAAUUGUUCUCAUUGUUGGGUUUUGAUUUCUAAAAAAAUAUUUAAGCAAAAAAACAAGUUACUAAAAAACAAAAUUCACAGAAGGAAAUGUAACUAAGAAUGAGUUACUUUGCCUUUAUCAUGUCGGAUUAAAGUUAAAAAAAAAAAAAGUCUCAGAUGUUCAUUCUGUCACCCCCUCCCCACCGACUUGCUGAACUAUUGCUUGGCCUGUUUAACUCAGAGCUGUUUAACUCAGAGCUCAUAUAUCAGGAUUAAUUUAAGGUUAAAUUCAGCUAUUUGCUCUGCCAUCAGUAAGCUUUGCAGUGGGCCUACUCAACAUUUAUCUACUAGUGAAACUCCAGGCUGUGUGAUAGUUAAAACACGGAGCUUACAGAAGAGGACUAGAAUAUCCAUUUUACACCAGAGUGGAGGAAGCAUGACUAUAUGCAAAUUUAGCACCAAUUAGAUGGUAGGAUUUGAAGGACUGUGGUCCCUGGAAUAUUCCAAAAGCAAAAAUGGAAAUGAUAGUGAUAACAUCUGAAGUGUGGUGGCAAGACAGUUAAAACAGUGCUAAUUUGGAGCCUCUGGGCACAGAACAGUACCAGGAGGCGAUCCACUGUGUCUUCUUUGGCAGCUGGCAGCUGGCAGACAAAGCAAAUAAUGAGUCUUUGGCUUGUUACUUUUCACCAUUCCAUAGUUUUCUCCAAUUUUGAAUAAACCCCCAAAACAAACAUCCUUCCUGCAUUGUCGUUUUACUGUAGCAGACCCUCAUAUAGCAAGUGUGCUACUGGCCCAACAGUCUACCACAGUGGAAACCACAGGAACUCAGGGUUGCCGGUGUACUUGCUUAAAGGUUAGCGUAGGCACAGCAUGGCAUUGGUAGGGGGCGCAUUCUUCAAAGACUCACAUGGUGAUUUCUUAUAGUCAGGGAGUUGAGCUGACUUAAUCAAGAUUAGAAGGAGGCAUGCUAGUGUGAGAAUAUCCUGUAAAAUACUCACCACUUGAAAGCAUUCCUGGCAAGCAUAUCAUUUACCUGAUAUAUAAUUUCAUUAAGCACCAAGAUUGUGCUGGUUACUUUCUAGAGAAAAGAUGAAAAGCUACCUACCUUAAUUAUCCUCAGACUUAAUUUCAUAUACCCAGAAAACAACUUUCCAGAAAAUAGUGGUAACCACAGCUACCUAAUUUAGAAUAGAUCCUCUGAAAACUUGCUAAGAGCAGUUGAGUGGUGAACGUCCAAAAAUGUACAACUUUUUUCUUUGCCUGCGUAAUUUUGUUUUUUUUCUUUAUUCCCACUAGAACACAUUCUCCUUACCCUCACUGGAACAACUGUAGAACAGAAACCUAAGGAAAUAUAGGAAGUGGGGAAGGAGGGAACAAAAUGAGAAAUUUAAUGUGAUUCCAAAUGUAAUCUUUAAGAACGUGAAUUGUGAAAAUUCUGAUCUCCCAAAGAUCAGGCAAUCAGAUACUUCUAAAUGUAGAAAUCUUUAGAUAAUAGCACGUAUUUUACCUGCAGGCUGAAUUUUAUGUUUGCAUCUUUUUUCCCCCUGCAUCUUUGAAAGUGAAAGCCGGUAAACCAGUUGCCAGAACGGAAAAGACUGUUUUAAUCACUGGAGCCUGCUAAAAAUGUAAAUAAUGCUGAUAAAUCAGUAAAAUUUUUGUAUAUUACUCAACCGAAUUGCACUUAAUCCCCAUUUCACAGACCCAGUUUAGGACACUUAGAACUUUCUUCGUCUUCUUGUCCACACCUUUUCCCUACCCACUUUUGAGAUUUCUCCUACUUUGUUUGUCCUAUCUUCUUUCCAGACCCCUUUUCUCCAAACUAGUAUUGACCAACACAUGGCACUUGAGGCUCAUGGUUUUGGGAUUUUUUUUCUUCACAUGCAGCCUAUGUUUCUUAUUUCUAUUCUAGAAGAUUAUAUUACAUUAAACUCAGCAUGACCUAUGAGAGUUCACAUGUCUCUCCUUUAGUUUAUGGUGACUGCAAAGGAUGCUCCAUUAGCUGAACUCCCUUAGCUCUUUAACUGUUAGUCAUUUCUUGAUUUGGAGUAAACAAUAAUAAAAUUUUCCUUUUCCUCUAGUGUGUUGAAUUUCCCAGUUAGUACCAAGAGGUAGUGCGAUGUAGAGCUCUAGAUCCAAAUGCUGUCUUGAAGAAACUAUUUAAAUAUUCUCAUUCUUAAUUUCCUCAUUAUUAUAAAAAGGAUAACAGUGUAUGUAAAGUGCUCAGCUACAUCACAGGUAGUUAAUAAAUGUUAGUCUCUCCCCUUCCUUUCCCUAUGAAGGAAAAAAUCUUAGUCAAUAAUUUAAAAAGUAAAUAUCUAUGAUGAAUAUAAAUAUAUUGGCUAUAAACCUUAAAUUAAUUUUGAGUACAAGUUACCAAAGUAAUGAAUUUGCUAUUUCCUCUGGUUUUAUAACACCCCAAUAUGUGAAUGUUCACACAUACACACCAAUUAAUACAGAUAAUUGGGGAGGGCACUUUAGUACUUGAAUAUUUCAGAAUAAAAGGGUUUUAUUUGAUGAUUUUAAAGUUUCCUGCUUGGAGUUUCAGCUCUAAAAUGUUUAUCAGAGAGAAGUUAUUGUGGUGUUUUUGGGUUUUAGGGGAGAAGAUAUUUAGGGAAUGUGAUACUUGAUGCAGAUAAUUUAUUGUAAUCAUUUUCAGAUUUUCAACAUUUUCUGAGUGGCUUUUUAAAUAGCCGCUAUACCUGGAGCUGAUGAGGAAAAUUUAAAUAAAUCCAUCAUGAAUGUUUUUCAAGGAGUGCAUAGAGACACAAAAUGAAACUCUAGGGCUCUGAGCAAUGUGAUUAUCACUCUGUACUUACGUAAUGCCUUUGUCAAUAACUUCAAGAUUUCUUUCUCAAAGUAGAAGAAAUAUAGUUGUUGAGAAAGCAUAUAUAAAAUUGCAAUGAUCUAUGCAUGGCAAACAGUAAAAUACCCAAUUGGACAUAUCAAAGGCAGGUUAUAGCUGCAAGUUACAGUUGGUCAGAAGGUCUCAGUGAGACUUUGCAUUGACUUGAGGUACAGACUUGUAAGAAAGGAAUCCUAGAAGUUUGUUUGCUCAGGUGAGUCCAGAUCACCACGAGAACAUUUUUUGCUAAACUAAAGAGUUCUGUGUUUUUAGUCUAAUGGUUCAAGGCUGUGUGAGUCUGUGGUCUUCGGUGCCUGUAAGUGCCACUAAGGCAAAUUGAGUGAUUUUAAAGGAGAAAGAGUUUAGAAGAUUAAAAGGAGAAAACCUCAACAUUAUUGUUGGUGUUCUAAGUGACAGGCUGAAUAAGAAGGGAAUCUUUAUUUAUUUUUUCAGCAUUUUGGUUUACUCCCACAUAACCACAUUAGAUCUAUCCAGAGGACAGUUCUCUUGAGGUCUCUCUGUCCUGUAAGAAAGGCAGAGGUGAAUAGUUGAGUUUAAAAUGGGUGAGAAAGGAGAUAGUUAUAUGUAACCAGCACACAUUUCUAAAAGAAUGAUAAAAAAAGAGAACACUAUUGGAUCCAAAUUGUUAGCAUGUCCUUGAAAGUAAAUGUAAGGACUCCUUGAAGUAAUCUGAACUAUACAUUGACAUCUUAAUGAAUUGCCUAGUUCAAAUAUUAUUAGGUCUAAUACAUUGUGAACUUUGUUAAACAUGGAUAUUUAAUAAUCAUUAAAAUAAACUUAGUUAUUUGUUACUGCCAGAAGUAGGUAGACCAUUUAUUAAAUUCAAUGUGAAAAAUAUACUUUAUGAAAUAUUUGCAUUAGUUGUGUAACAGACAUCUUAAAAAAUGGGCAACAUCAAAUAAGCCAGUCAUUGUAUGUAUAACUAUAAAGAAAAAAGUGUUAGACAUGCAUAUUGCAUUUUUUAGCCUCCUCCUCAUGUUAAUGGUGGAUGUUAAAGCUUUCCUUGGUUGUAUAUCGAUUUUAUUAUCCCAAGCAUGUAUUGAAUCCAUGAUCUGCUUAUAAUUCUCAUCAUGCUUGGUAUUAGUACUAAACAGAGAACCAAUAUAUUAUGCCGUAGAGUUUGGCACUCUGUUUAGUAAGUCAUUACCACUACCUCACCUUACCUGGCAGAGCUGCUUGUUUUGUCCAUGUGACUUCUUAUUUUUGCUAGUUAUGCCUAUAGAAAGGUCAUUCAACCCAAUAAUGGCUUCUCAUUUAGUCUAGAAAUCAGACAAAAGCUUUGCAGCUGUGAAAUGCAGCCCAUUUAAAAAUUAACCUAUUGUAAAUUCUUAAUGAUUGAGAAAUUCUGCAAUUUGCUGUGAUUUGUGGUUUGUGCUGCAAUUAGAAUAGCAAACAGCAGAGAUGAUGCAGUCAGAAUGACGUGCAUUUGGGAAGUGAAGAGAAAGAAACUUUAGCAGAUACUGUGCUGGGUUCAAGCCAAUGUAUUAUGCCCUUCUGCCCUCAUCAGUCAUAUAUCACUUUGUCUCCCACCUUUAGACUCUUCCAAGUGAAAUGUAAUCCUUGGAAAUAAUUACAUAAAUUACUGUUUUAAAUACUUAAAUACUCAAGAGGUAAAAUUGUCCAUAAGUGUAGUCUACCUUUUCCUCCUUUAAUAUUUUCUCACCCUAGAGCCUAGAUUCUUAGCGGAAAGAAGGACAUAGAUUUUUGAUUCAUGAAGACCUAGAAUUCAAAUUUUGUUAAUAAAACAAAUCAGCUCUGUAUCCUCAUGCAAAUUACUUAAACUCUCUGGCUUCAGCUUCUACAUCUGCGUAUCUCACUGGACUCUUGUACAGAUUAAAUUAGAUACUGUUUUACUUAGUAGGGAUACAAUAUGCUUCUUCACCAUUUACUGUCUAUUAACCCCUGAUCAAAUUAUAUAACUCCUCUAUGCCUCUGUUUCCCUCUGUGAAAUGGGGAUAUUAAUACCUACUUCAUAGGGUUGUUGUGAGCAUUAAAUAAAUAAUGCAGAACCCUUAGAACAGUACUCUACAUCUAGUUAGUAUUCCAUAAUUAUUAACCAGUGGAUUGACAAAUCAAUAAUCAACAAAUAACUUACAAUGAUAGAUAAUGUAAAUGAAACAUGUAGGGUACACUAAGACAAUUUAUUAGAGCUAGAAAAAUAAGCAGGGCUAUGUCAUUUAGUGCUUUGUAAUGGGAAGCCACUGACAAGGAUGACGUGAUUGAAAUUACUUUUUUUUUAACUGACCUGUUUCUUGUUUUUUUUGUAUUAUUUUUGUUUUUAUUCACCUUCUACAUACAGUAAUUCACUCCUUUUGGUGUUUGAGCUUAGACAAGUGCAUAUAGGCAUAGAGCCACUACUAGAAUCAAGACAAAAUAGUUCCAUCACCAGCCCCCACCACCGCCAUUAAAAAAGAGCCCCACAUGACAACCCCUUUGUAAUAAAUUGCUUUCCCCACUCCUAAAUCUUAGUCUGCUUUCUGUUGAUAUAGUUUUGCGUUUUCCAGUAUGUCAUGUAAAUGGAAUCACAUACUCUAUAGCUUUUAAAGUCAAGCUUCUUCAGUUCAGCUCAAAGCAUUUGGAAUUCAACCAUAUUGUUGUAUUUAUCAAUAGUUUACUAAUAGUUCUUAUUCCUGAGUAGUAUUUCAUUUUAUGGCUAUACUGCAAUGUGUUUAUUCACCAUUUGAAGGGCAUUUAAGUUAUUCCCAGUUUUGGAUGGUCACAAAUAAAUAUACUGUAAACAUUUUUAUUCAAGUUUCUGUGUGAACAAAUGUUUUCAUUUAUCUUGGGUAAAAUAUCUAGGAGUAAAAUUGCCGGCUCUUAUGGUAAAUGUAUGUUUGACUUUAUAAAGAAACUGCCAAACUGUUUUCCAACAUGGUUAUACAAUUUUACAUUUCCACUAGCAAUAUAUGAGAGUUCAGUUGCCUUGCAUUGUUGUCAACACUUUGAUAUUGUCAAUAUAUUUUAUUUUAGACAUUCUAAUAGGUAUAUAUAGUAUCUCAGUGUGAUUUUAAUUUGCAUUUUCCUAAUGACUAAAAUGAUUUUGAACAUACAGUAUUUUUAUUUGCUUAUUUGUCAUCUAUAUAGCUUCUUUGGUAAAGUGUCUGUUCAAAUCUUUUGCCCAUUUUUUAAAUUUAGUUGUUUGUUUCUUACUGAGUUUUAAGAUUUUUUUCAUGUGUUCUGGUACAAAUUCUCUGUCAGAUAUGUGAUUUGCAAAUAUUUUAUUAUAAUCUAUGCUUUGUCUUUUCAUUCUCUUAACAAUAUAUUUAGAGAGCAUAAGUUUUAAAUUUUGAUGCAGUUUAUCAGUUUUUUAUUUUAUGAAUCAUGUUUUUGGUGUCAUUUCUAAGAAAUUUUGCCUAACCCUAGGUCACAAAGAUUUUCUUUUAUGUUUUCUUUUAGAAGUUUUAUAAUUUUCAGUUCUAUAUUUAUUUAGGUGUACUUUACACUUUGAUUUUUGUGUAAUGUGAAUGAUGUAGAUUGAGAUGCGUAUUUUAUGUAUGAAUAUCCAAUUUUUCCAGUACCAUUUAUUGAAAAGACUAUCAUUUCUUCAUUGCAUUGCCUUUGUGCCUUGGUCAAAUAUCAAUUGACCUUAUAUUUGUGGAUUUAUUUGUGAGCUCUCUAUUCUGUUUCACUGAUCCAUGUGUCUCUCUGCUUACCAAUAAUACCACACUGUCUUGAUAACUAUAGCUUUAUACUAAGUUUUGAGAUCAGUUAGUAUCACUUCUUCAAAUUUGUUCUUUUUCAAAAUUGUUCUAGUUUCUUUGGCUUUCCACAUAAAUCAGGUUGUUGAUAUCCAUUAAAAAAUCCUUUGGGGAUUUUGCUUGUGAUUAUGUUAAAUCUAUAGAUCACUUUGGGAAGAAUUGACAUCUUUACAAUAUUGAAUCUUUCAAUCCAUGAACAUGGUGUAUAUCUCUUUUUAUUUAGGUUCUCCUUGAUUUCUUUCUUUCAUCAGUAUUUUGUAGUUGUCAACAUGCAGAUCCUGCACAGAUUAUUUUUAGAUUUAUACCUAUUUCAUGUUUUUUAGUUGUGUUACUAUAAAUUAUACUUUAAAAUUUUAAAUUUCCAACUGUUCAUUGUUGGUAUAUAGAAAUUCAAUUGGUUUUAGUAUUCUUAUAGUCUGCAUCCGUUUAUGUAUGUAUUUAACAUCUUUGGAUUCUGCAGCCUUGUUAAACUUAUUGGUUCUAGGAGCCUCUUUGUAUAUCCUUCUAUGUAAGUAAUCAUGUUGUCUGUGAAUAAAGACAGUCCUAUUUCUUCCUUUUCAA